GCUUUCGCCGCCUGGGAGCCGUCCGGCGCAGCAGUUUCUAGGUCCCCACUGUCCCCGCCGUCCCGCCCCUUCGCGUCCCGGGAACCGGCUGGCUUCCGAGCCGCACUCGCCGAUCCUCCAGGCAUGCCCCGCUACGAGCUGGCUUUAAUCCUGAAAGCCAUGCAGCGGCCAGAGACUGCUGCUACUUUGAAACGUACGAUAGAGGCCCUGAUGGACAGAGGAGCAAUAGUGAGGGACUUGGAAAACCUGGGUGAACGAGCGCUUCCUUAUAGGAUCUCUGCCCACAGUCAGCAGCACAACAGAGGCGGGUAUUUCUUGGUGGAUUUUUAUGCACCCACCGCAGCUGUUGAAAGCAUGGUGGAGCACUUGUCUCGAGAUAUAGAUGUGAUUAGAGGGAAUAUUGUCAAACACCCUCUGACCCAGGAACUAAAAGAAUGUGAAGGGAUUGUCCCAGUCCCACUCGCAGAAAAAUUAUAUUCCACAAAGAAGAGGAAGAAGUGAGAAGAUUCGCCAGAUUUUAGCCUUAUAUGUAAUUCCUUCACAUUUGGGCAGCAUGGACGAGAAGGAAGAAUUUGCAAGUUUGGCCUUUAUAUAAGCAUGUGUUGCAGGUGCUGUUUGAUUUUUCUAAGGUAUUUUUAGCCCUUGAUCCCCUUUGCUUGCGAGAGGUGGGGAACUGCUCACUGACAGCUUCUCUGUAACCUGCAGUACCAGUGGAUCGUUCUUGAUUUUGUUUUCAUUAGUGUCAUUUCUUUGUCAUUGAGGACUUUUCCCCUUACAACAGUAACACCAUUUUUUGAAGAGCAAAACUUAUAAUACCUCCUGGGAUUGUGAGCUAGUCAUUCAGCCUGUGUAACCAUGUGGAAAUAAAAAUUGACGACCAAUGUAUUAUAUGGACAACUUUUGCUUUGAGUAAUAAACUUGAUUGUAGGAA